AUCGCGGGCGCGACGCCUGAGGGACAGUCUGGGGUUUGGCUGUCCGGACGGUGCAGCGGCGAGGCCGGCCGCGAAGAUGCCAGUGGCGGUGAUGGCGGAAAGCGCCUUUAGUUUCAAAAAGUUGCUGGAUCAGUGCGAGAACCAGGAGCUCGAGGACGCUUGAUGUAAUGGGCAGAAUCAGAAUGCUUCAGGAAUCUGUCGAAUUUGUUUCUUAUAAUAGCCCCUGGAGGAAUUGCUACACCCCCAGUGUAUGGUCAGCUUCUAGCUUUAUAUUUGCUCCAUAAUGACAUGAAUAAUGCAAGAUAUCUUUGGAAAAGAAUACCACCUGCUAUAAAAUCUGCAAAUUCUGAACUUGGGGGAAUUUGGUCAGUAGGACAAAGAAUCUGGCAGAGAGAUUUCCCUGGGAUCUAUACAACCAUCAACGCUCACCAGUGGUCUGAGACGGUCCAGCCAAUUAUGGAAGCACUUAGAGAUGCAACAAGGAGACGCGCCUUUGCCCUGGUCUCUCAAGCGUAUACUUCAAUCAUCGCCGAUGAUUUUGCAGCCUUUGUUGGACUUCCUGUAGAAGAGGCUGUGAAAGGCAUAUUAGAACAAGGAUGGCAAGCUGAUUCCACCACAAGAAUGGUUCUGCCCAGAAAGCCAGUUGCAGGGGCCCUGGAUGUUUCCUUUAACAAGUUUAUUCCCUUAUCAGAGCCUGCUCCAGUUCCCCCAAUACCCAAUGAACAGCAGUUAGCCAGACUGACGGAUUAUGUGGCUUUCCUUGAAAACUGAUUUAUCACUCUGAGUUCAAGAUUCAUCUUCAGAAUCCUGUAUACUGACAAACGUAGAAAUGUAAAGUUUGUAUUUUCAAUUUAUUGGAUGGCUUAAGCACCUCAGCAUUCCUUACUAUGUGAUAAAAUACAUAUAGAAUAUAAGAUAUACUAUAUACAUUUUGUCCAUAAACGUUAUGCUGAAUAGUUGUUGAAACAGUUCUCAUUUUGUAGUAUUUAAUAAUCUGGAUGGAGCCUGUCAGUAUUACAGUUAGUUUUCUAGUGACUCAUAAAAUAAGAUUUCCUGUUUCAUGUAGAAUAGUGUUUGUCAACUGUCUUUUCUCUGUCCCAGCACAUGCCGUACUCUUAUAUGUACCAUUGGUUGAUAAUUAUAAUGAUUCAUUUGGACUUGAAGAAAGAUUGUCCCCAGGCACAGUAUCUGAAUCACUGGGGAUUAUGAUUCACCCUCUUUGGAGAACAUGCUCUCUUUUCACCCCCCACCUCCUGAGAGCCACUAAUGUAAGAUACAGAAACAUAGCUGAGGAACAAAUAGACCAUUUCCAUACUAAACCAGUUUGUUAACUUUAGAUUUUUUCCAAUAGUGUGAGUAUAUCCAUUGCUGGCAGUGGAGGGCUUGCCAUGAAAAUGCAACUUAUUUAAGACAUUUAUGAGACAUAUUAACUUGUGCUGUCGCCUUUUAGAAGGAGAAACUUAAGUGUGGAAUGCAUUAUAUGGGCAAAGAAGCUAUGAAGAUACAUGAUACACUUUGUACAACUAUCCUGCAGCCCAUUGGUUGCUUAUAUUUAUCGCUUGGCUCAAGUUCUGCCCUUUGGAGAAAUACUGAGCAAGUCUUUCAUUCUCUGUGUGACAGCCCUCUGAAUAUUUGAAGUUGUUUGUUGUAACUUAAGGUUAUAACAGCCCUUAGUUCAUUUACUCUGCAUUUGUUCAAUAAAUAUUUAACUGAAUUCUUCAAUUAUUUCAUCUAAGAUAGUUUCUGGAAAUUUCACUCUCGAUCUUUCUGUGGACACAAUCUAUUUUGUCAUUGUGUCUAUAUGAAUCUCUUAAGUAGAAAUGAGUUGUAUGGUGAAUCUGUGUAGUGAUAAUUAUAUAAUUUAUUUAUUUUGAAUGCAUUUUAGUGGCUAUUUCAGUUUUUCUUAACAUAUAUGGGAAUACUUUUUGAAUUGCAAUUUUAUUUAACCCGGAUAGGUAAGUCAUAUUAAAAUUCCUUGUUUUACAGUUGAGGAAAUGGGAAUUCAAGAAGUCAGAGGAUCAGGAGAGUGAUCAAGAGAAUGACAGUGCCAGUUUUUUUAACUUCCAGGUAUUAAGUACAAAUUGUAUCCAUGGUUAUUUUUUAAAAGCAGAUUAGAGUCAAUCCAAAUAUUCAUUAAUAGGGGAUUGUUUGAAUAAACAGCAGUGUAGACUACGCAGGUGUAAAAGGAGUGAAGAUCUCUAUACUAAACUGGAAUGAUCUCCAGAGUGAGAACAUAGAAAGCACAUGUAGUUUAUAUGGUUAUUUUGAGGGUAACAAAAGGAGAAUGAUUACAAUUAUAUAUAUGUACAUAUUUCCUUAUAUUUCAAAACUAAGCAAUUGGGGGAUAUAUACAAAAUGAAUAUAAUAGUUCCCUAAAGAGGAAGGAGAGGACAGUGAACUACUACAUAGAGAAAAAAUAAUCUCAAGUGAUCAAACACAAUAUUUCAAUUUUACAUUGUCAGUGGGAUAUACACUAAGGACAGAAAAAAAUCUUAGACUAAUGAAUGUGGUUUUUCAUGAUUAAUUUCACAAAAUCUUGAUAUCUUUUUUAUUAUUAAAAGUAUAGAUUAAAUUAAUAAUCAUGUAACAUUAGACCCCAGUAAUCUUAAAUUUGACAUGGAAACCUCAUUAUAUGCUUUAUUUUUCUUUGUAAACAGUAAAUAUUUCCCACUCCUGUCUACAUGAAAAGGUCUAGAGUAAUUACAGUUCAGUAACAAUGAGCACCACUAGUACCCAGAUGGUGUUCUUUCAUUUUCAUUUGCAAUUAAAAGGAAUCAGAACUUAUUUGCAAAACAGCUAAUAGUUCCAGGGCAGUAAGUGUACAAGUUCAUAUCUGGUACAAGAUGUCCAGGAUUCAAGGAGGCUCUUAAAGACUUGGGAUUCUGUCAAAGGGUUAUACAAGCCAACUUGAAGGGAUUUCUACAGGCCAUGUAAAAAUGAGACAGUUUGAGCAUGAAAUAUUUGUAUAUGUGUCUGUUUUUAACUCUUAAUAACCUCAUCACUGUACAAGAAAGGCAGGGUAAGUGCUUGAUUUCACUUCCCUUUAUUAUCAGUUCUCAGGACAAAUUGAUAUGCUGCCAAUCUCUAAAGCAACAAAAUCGAACCUGUAGGGUAGUCAAAAAGCUCAUGCUGGAAAAUUCCACCGAAUAAAGAUAAAAGUUAGAAAAACGGUACUUGCAGCCCUUAAUGAAACAAAGAAGGGAUCAUGGAAAUAUAUAUCAAUGCUGUUGAGACCACAGGGUAAGAAAUUGAGAUUGAGCAUGAAAUAUGUCCAGUACAUCCAUCAGCCUGUCUUUGUGCUCUGGCUAUUUCUGAGCCAGCCAUCUGUGUACAAGUGUAGCCUGACAGCACCCUGUUUCAGAUCCAUUGGAUAUCUCUAAAAUUUGCUCUGGGACUUACCCUGGCACUACUAUCAGGAUGCCCACACAAACCUGAUUGGGCAGCCCAUCAGCAGUUGUGAACAUGACAUGGUGAAUAAACACUCUCUUCCUUGUCUCAGGGCA